UUUGGAGUUUCCAAGAUCUGGGGCUGGGGAUUGGGGGUAUCUCACCAUCUGUCUCAGAGGUUGGGCACAGAAAGGGUGGCUGGAGCUUGCUAUCCUUCCCAGGGGUUCUGUCCAGGGCUGCCUCCCUGCUUCUACCCCAAACACCCUCCUAUUGCCGUUUUCUGUGUCCCAGGCUUUGGGCAUGGCGGUCGGGGUGAAACUGUGUUUGGGAAUUUGCACAAGGCUUAGGAAAGAAACUGUGUAGCUUUGGGGUUUCUAGGAUGUAAAAUGAAAAGGGUGGAUCCUUAAGAUGUCAGUGAACUUGACUGGCACCUCAGUCAUUCAAGGGACUGGCCAAGUCCCUUAAAACCGGCAGAAUCUGAAGACCCUUCCCAGCAGCAAGGGCAGGGACUCGUUCAUAUCCUUUGAGGGUCUGUGAGCCUCUCUGAUGGCCUCUAAGCCUUCAGAAUUGUGGAUUUUGAAGUAGAUCCCAUUGCUACUGAAAGGAACCAAACAACAAUAAUUCUUCCCCAAUAAUUCUUGAGUUAAGUCAGAGUAUCUCAAAUAGGACCCGAGUGGUUUUAGGGCCCAGGAGUUUUUCCAUUAAGAAGUAGGCUGCCCGGGUGAUGUGUUGAGCAGGGGUUGCAUGUAAGUCACUUUCUGUGGUGGCUUUAUCGCCAUACACUUGGAUUUGUUUUUGUUUUUGCAAAAAUUCCUUUUAGAAAGAACAUGAUCAUCUCUAAAGCAUCUUUCAUGCAAGGCUGGGUUUGCACCUAUAGGGUUUUGGGUUAGGUGGGCUCUGCGUAUUUUUCUAGCCCUCUGUUGCCAGGCCAUAGAAGAGACUCAGGUAUUAUUUAAAGGAAGAGGGAAUGAUGGCGUUGUUUUCCUCCAAUUCUUCCAUUUUCCAGACAAGGAACUUGAUUGACAUUCAGAGGGAGGGGUUAAGUGACUUACCUAUGGCCUCGGGUGAGCUAUUGGCGUCUGUAUCCCCAACCCCAUCCUAUCUUGGUCAGUUUACCAGCCUCUCAAUUUAGGACACUUUGGGCUUUUCUGCCUGUCGUCUUCCUCAUUUGGCUAAGCUGCUCACAUCAAAUUCCUUCUAAUCUUUGCUGUUCCUUAGAUCCUUCCAAGGGCUUGUUGUUUCUUCCAUGCACGCCUCCCCCAUAAUCUGGUAUCUUCUUAGGGGAGUCUUCUGCAUCGGAAGUGCCCUCCGCGCUGUCCCAGAGAAGCAGAAAGUGAUCUGAAUUAGCCCUUGUAAUAGGUUCCAUCCAGAGCUUGAGGAAGUGAACUUAAGAACAAGGAUUAUCCUUCUGUCCCACCCAUCUUCCCUUACACAACAGCAUGCUUAAGAGUCAGAUUACACAGGCCUCCUCUUUCUGGCCAUGUGACCUUAGACAGAUUACUUAACCUCUCUGUUCCUCGAUUCCCUUGUCCAUCCAUCAAUUGGGCAUACUAAUAUCCACCUCUUAAGGUGAUUCUGGGAAUGAAAUAAAGUGCUGUGCACAGUGCCUGGCCUAUAGUAGUCAAUAAAUGUUAGUAUUCUUGUCAUCAUAACCAUAAUUGUUCCACUCUGGGUUUUAGAGAAGCGGGAUGGAGGAGAAACAGGAAAUAGGAGAGAUUUUCAGUCCACAGAGUAAAAGAUAAAAAAACUUACUGCAGUCAAUUUCGUGUUUCUAUCAUAGUAUUAAUAAUUGCUUUUUUUUUUUUCUAAAUAUCUGCAACAUACCUAAUGUCUGUUAUCUCAUUUUCUCUUUUCCGCUACAUAGUUCUUUUGGCUGUUUUAUAGAGAAAGAAGCUGGACUCAGAGAUAGAGCCUUCCUAAGGUUACACAGUCGAUAGGAAGCAGAGCUGGGAUUUAAACCCUGGUCUGUGUAAAAUCAGAGCUGGCAUUUUAUUUUUAUUUUUUCCUCUACGAGAGGCUGCCUCUCUCUUUCCCCUGCUGUCAGAAAUGUUAUUCAUAGAUUUCUGGAUCUGACCUUAGAAGUCGUCUAGUCCAAAUUCCCGCUCAGCGCAUCAGUCCCCUCCCCGCUCACCAGGCACUCCCUCAUUCGGCUUCUCCUUGAAGACAUUCAUUCGGCAAGAGGGAGCUUUGAUGUGCAUACUCUUGGCCAGCUUGUAUUAUUAGAAAGCUGUUAGGUCAUGAGGCACACUUGCCCCUCCUGUUGCCAUGCCACACUUAGGAGACGUUGCCUUGGUGCCAGGAGAAAUUGUCGGUCCAUGGGUUGCUGCCCACUUGGCUUCCUGAGCGGUAUCUGGGGAACUGGAAAUGGUGAGAGGCAGCCUGCACCAGGCUCAGAGCUGGGCAGGACCAGGCUGUCAGGUGCCAUCAUUGGCCAGAAAAGAAUUGCAGCCUCUGGGGCAACUUGGUGUUAGGCAGUAUUAUGAUCAAGAGAUGCAGUGGAAAUUCCCCAGCUACCACUCUCCAUUCUUCAUGGGAGCAAAUUCCUCUCCAUCCUUCUCAUUUCUUUCCUGAUUGGCAGAUGCUCCCCCACUUCCUCUGCAGCCAGAAGUAAAUGCCUUCUGGCACCCAGCAUCUCUUAAAUUACAUCACUGCCACCACCAUCAUCAUCGCCAUCAUUGCCAUCACUAUGGCAACUCUAUUUAUUCACCUCCUCUUGCCAUGCCCUAGCCACCAUGCAGAGCACUUUAUGUGUAUAACUCAUUACUUGUCGCAGGAAUCCUGUGACUAGUCAUGAGCAUCUCCCACAGUAUGGAGAAGGAAGCUGGAGCACAGAGAGGUGAAAUGACCUGCCCAAGGUCACACAGCAAGCAAGUGGCAGAGCCAGAAUUUGUCCCUAAGACUGUUUGAGCCCAAAGCCAGCAGGCUAAACUGCCUUUUAAAGUUUUGUUUUGUUUUGUUUUGUUUUUUGUUUUUUUGUGGUUUUGAGAUGGAGUCUCGCUCUGUUACCCAAGCUGGAGUGCAGUGGCGCAUCUCGGCUCACUGAAGCCUCUGCCUCCUGGGUUCAGUGAUUUUCCUGCCUCAGCUUCCCAAGUAGCUGGGAUUAUGGGUGCCCGCCACCACACGCGGCUAAUUUUUGUAUUUUUAGUACAGACGGGGUUUCGCCAUGUUGGCAGGCUGGUCUUGAACUCCCAACUUCAGGUCAUCCACCCGCCUCGGCCUCCCAAAGUGCUGGGAUGACAGGCAUGAGCCACCACGCCCGGCCCGCCUCUUGGAGUUCUGUGCCACCUGCUACCUCCCUGCCUUCCUGGGUUAUGCUAUCUCUGAGCCAAGUGCAGAAGAUUCAGCCAGAAACAAAAAUGCUGACUCUCUGCAGACAUCUCCUGAGACUGGUUCCUGGGGUUCGGCCAGUCACUGUUAUCUCAGGCAUGCUUUGAUCCACUCUCCCAGAUGGGAAGGUCUCUCUUGUUCUGCCUCGCUCUAGUCUUGCCUCGCUCUAGUCUAGGUCCCAGAAGUCUGAGUGAGUGAAGCCGAGGCUCUGAAUCACAACUCUUUGGGAUAUCAAACCAGGAGGGGCUCUUGGCCUGUCUGACAUCCCUCAAGUUUUGGGAUCACCUAAAACAGACAUUUAUUGCACUCAUCAAACUUGACCCUGGGACUGAGUUCCUUCACCUCCAGCCUGAGUAGCUGCUUCCUCUUUGAGGAACCGGAAUACUGCACCACCCUCUCUAGGCCUGGAAGGGGCUUAGGAAGUUGGAAGGGAGUCUCGGUCUGUAGUCCCACAGGGCUUUGGGGAGAGGAAGCAGGAGAGGACACGGUGGGCAGGGGGUUGUUCUGAGUCUCAACCUGGAAGGACAGGCUGCCCCUGGGUCUUGGGAUGUUCUCCUAAGCAGGGCCUUCUUUGCCCUGGAGGAAUCUGACUGCAAGUAGAAUGCAGUAGGAUGGAAGGAUAGGGUGCGCAGACCUGCACUUCUCAGACAAAGAGCCCUCAGGGUUUCAGCUCCUGUCGCUCCUUGGGAAGGUCCUACUCUAGCUAAAUCCCCCCACAUUGAAGGAAGGUAUGUAAGCUCCAGGCCGAAGGCAGAGUGCAGGCCGAAGGCAGAGUGCAGGCCGAAGGCAGAGUGCAGGCCGAAGGCAGAGUGCAGGAGCUGGAUUCUGUAGAGGCACUGGGCAUCCCGGGAGGCUGGGGAGAACUGAAUGUUGUGUCUGGAAGCUGCUGUUGUCCUAAGGGGAAGGUCUGUGGGCAGUGCGGACUUUUUAUAGCCGCAUGGGAACCUUCAGGGCGGAGGAUCGGCUGGUCAGGGCCUGGGAGCACAGCUAUAUUAGGUAAGCAGAGAAGGGCCCUGCCUUAGCCUCUAGAGGUCCGGCACUCUGGGCCAGGCAGGGAGCCAGGGAAGGCGGGAGGGAGGAAAAGGAGAACUGGUGGAUGGCAGAGAGUGUCUAGUCUUGAAAUCACAAACUGGGUGGAAUCCUACCUACAGAUGUGCCUUGUGUGGCCCACCCGGUGCUUUAAAUCAGAUCUGGUUACACUGGGCUGGAGUUAAGUAGUGCUACCUCUUCAGAGGGGUCACCAUCUCAGGCUAGGUGCGGUGGCUCACGCCUGUAAUCCCAGCACUUUGGGAGGCUGAGGCAGGAGGAUCACCUGAGAUCAGGAGUUCGAGACCACCCUGGCCAACAUGGUGAAACCCCAUCUCUGCUGAAAAUACGGAAAAAAAAAUUAGCCAGUGUGGUGGUGGGUGCCUGUAAACCAAGCUACUCAGGAGGCUGAGGCAGGAGAAUCACUUGAAUCCGGGAGUCAGAGGUUGCAGUGAGCCAAGAUCACGCCACUGCACUCCAGCCUGGGCGACAGAGUGCACUAGCCACACACGAAAAAGGAGGGGGCAUGUUUCCACUUUGCCCCAGUCCCCACCUCUCACACCCUGCCUGCUUCAUUUAUGUCAGCAAUGGCACCUGCAUGUGCAACCUCUGGUCUGGCAGACCAGCCAAGCCUGGUCUCCAUGCUGCCAGCUCCGAUUGCCCUCACUGCCUUCCAGCGGGGAUCUGGCUGGAGUAGGACAAGUCUGUUUGGGAGCUGGGAGGAAUGACUUAGCCCUGGAGAUUGACUGAAUUGGGAGGUUGGGAGCAUUUUGGGAAAGGAUGUUGUCUCAUUAGGCUCUGAGUGAACACUUCCCAUUGGUGAGAAUAGAAGCCCCCCGCUGCCCCUGUCUCUUCAUGCACUUGGGUGUGUGAUUCUGUGCAUAUGUAUGUGCCAGUGCGUGCGUGCGUGUGUGUGUGUGUGUGUGUGCGCAUGUGCCACACAGAGGGCAUCACAUUCAGCUCUCCCCGGAACCACCAUUUCCGUCAAGGAUUGGAGACUCUGUCUGUUGGACCAAUUUGAUGCCUGUGCACGCUCAGGGCUCUCUGAACCCCGCUCCUUGACUCUCAGGGUCCCCUCUUGCGGAAAGCCCCUCCCGGGACCAGGAGCCAGGCUGGGCAGGGAGGUGACACCCUGCCUCUCUUUUGCAUUUGCUUGGUGCUGGCUGAAGAUGUGCCAGGAGGAACAGACCAGCUACAUGGUGGUGCAGACGAGCGAGGAGGGGCUGGCGGCUGACGCCGAGCUCCCGGGACCGCUCCUGAUGCUGGCCCAGAACUGCGCAGUCAUGCACAACCUGCUGGGCCCUGCCUGCAUUUUCCUGCGCAAGGGCUUCGCUGAGAACAGGCAGCCUGAUAGAUCACUGCGACCAGAGGAAAUUGAAGAGCUCCGAGAGGCCUUCAGAGAAUUCGACAAGGACAAGGAUGGCUACAUCAACUGCCGGGAUCUGGGCAACUGCAUGCGCACCAUGGGCUACAUGCCCACCGAGAUGGAGCUCAUCGAACUGUCCCAGCAGAUCAACAUGAACCUGGGUGGCCAUGUAGAUUUUGAUGACUUCGUGGAGCUAAUGGGGCCUAAACUCCUGGCAGAGACAGCAGAUAUGAUUGGUGUAAAGGAACUGCGAGAUGCUUUCCGAGAGUUUGACACCAAUGGUGAUGGGGAAAUAAGCACCAGUGAGCUGCGAGAGGCUAUGAGGAAGCUCCUGGGUCAUCAGGUGGGACACCGAGACAUAGAGGAAAUUAUCCGAGAUGUGGACCUCAAUGGGGAUGGACGAGUGGACUUUGAAGAGUUUGUCCGGAUGAUGUCCCGCUGAGGCCGCGAGGGCCCCUCCAGGACUGCCAAGCUCCCAAAGGCGGGGCUAAGAGGAGCUAGAGCUUGCCUCACCCGCUGUAGCCGCCGAGAGCCCAGGAUGUACUGGCGGAUGGGGCCUGCCUGCACCCCGGGGAGGCGCCCACCCCGGACCCCCACCCCUCCGCACUGUGAAAGACUAACUCCUGCAACUGGAAAGCGGGGGCGCCCGCCGACGAGGAGGCCACCGUGCCAAGCCGGCAGAGGUCAUGCCAGGCGCCAAGGGCCAUGUGCCCAGCUGCUGCUGGCUGGGUGGGCCAGGGAGCCCGCCAGCAGACCCCACACAGCAUGUCCGCCCCAGGGCAAAGCCUCCCACCUUCGCUCUGCGCCCGUCCCAGCUCGCCUCAGCCCUGUUAUCUCAGAACCAAUAAAAAUAUUUCCAAGAGCAA